GGAGUCGCGGACACUUCCGCUCGGGGACUGAGGUUGCUGCAGUUUUUCCGCGAUAGUUUGGGGCAGUUCCGCGCGUUGCAGGCCCUUCUGAAUUUCCUGGACCUACGCAUUGGAUCCUCAAAGAACUGGUGAUCGAAUUAGGGGAAAAGGGGCCUCGUCGGAGAGUAGAGCUGAAUACCACUAGAAACAUACCUGUAACCAGAGACAGCUGAUUAUAGCUUUCUGCAGCAAGGAAGCCCACGUACCAGGGGCUGUCUUGGCACAAUUCUGCUUUCCCAGGAACUGCAUCACUCAGGACUCUGCAAGUUUCCAGAAGUAAGAGGGAAAAUGACCACGUUCAAGGAGGCAAUGACCUUCAAGGACGUGGCUGUGGUCUUCACUGAGGAAGAGCUGGGGCUGCUGGACCUUGCUCAGAGGAAGCUGUAUCGAGAUGUGAUGCUGGAGAACUUCAGGAACCUGCUCUCAGUGGGACAUCAAGCAUUCCACAGGGAUACUUUCCACUUCCUAAGGGAAGAAAAGAUUUGGAUGAUGAAGACAGCAAUCCAAAGGGAAGGGAAUUCAGGAGACAAGAUCCAAACUGAGAUGGAGACUGUUUCAGAAGCAGGAACACAUCAAGAGUGGUCCUUCCAGCAAAUCUGGGAAAAAAUUGCAAGUGAUUUAACCAGGUCUCAAGACUUGAUGAUAAAUAGCUCUCAGUUCUCCAAAGAAGGUGAUUUCCCCUGCCAGACUGAGGCAGGACUAUCUGUAAUUCACACAAGACAGAAAUCUUCCCAGGGCAAUGGAUAUAAACCAUCCUUCAGUGAUGUCUCCCACUUUGAUUUUCAUCAACAAUUACACUCAGGAGAGAAAUCUCAUACGUGUGAUGAGUGUGGAAAGAACUUUUGUUACAUCUCAGCCCUUCGUAUUCAUCAGAGAGUCCACAUGGGAGAGAAAUGCUAUAAGUGUGACGUGUGUGGUAAGGAAUUCAGUCAGAGUUCACAUCUGCAAACUCAUCAGAGAGUCCACACUGGAGAGAAACCGUUCAAAUGUGUGGAAUGUGGGAAAGGCUUCAGUCGUAGAUCAGCACUUAAUGUUCAUCAUAAAUUACACACAGGAGAGAAACCUUAUAAUUGUGAGGAAUGCGGGAAGGCCUUCAUUCACGAUUCCCAGCUUCAAGAACAUCAGAGAAUCCAUACGGGGGAGAAGCCAUUCAAAUGUGAUAUAUGUGGUAAGAGCUUCUGUGGUAGAUCAAGACUUAAUAGGCAUUCCAUGGUUCACACGGCAGAGAAACCAUUCCGAUGUGAUACGUGUGAUAAGAGCUUUCGUCAGAGAUCAGCACUUAAUAGUCAUCGCAUGAUCCACACAGGAGAGAAACCAUACAAAUGUGAGGAGUGUGGAAAAGGCUUUAUUUGUAGGCGAGAUCUUUAUACGCAUCAUAUGGUCCACACGGGAGAAAAGCCAUAUAAUUGUAAAGAGUGUGGGAAGAGCUUCAGAUGGGCCUCGUGUCUUUUGAAACAUCAGCGAGUCCACAGUGGAGAAAAACCAUUCAAAUGUGAAGAAUGUGGGAAAGGAUUUUACACAAAUUCACAAUGCUAUUCCCACCAGAGAUCCCAUAGUGGAGAAAAACCAUACAAAUGUGUGGAGUGUGGGAAGGGCUACAAAAGGAGGUUGGAUCUUGACUUUCACCAGCGCGUCCAUACAGGAGAGAAACUGUAUAAUUGUAAGGAAUGUGGGAAGAGCUUUAGUCGGGCCCCAUGUCUUUUGAAACAUGAGAGACUCCACAGUGGAGAAAAACCAUUCCAAUGUGAAGAGUGUGGGAAGAGAUUUACUCAAAAUUCACAUCUUCAUUCCCAUCAGAGAGUUCACACUGGAGAAAAGCCAUACAAAUGUGAGAAGUGUGGAAAGGGCUACAAUAGUAAGUUUAAUCUUGAUAUGCACCAGAAGGUCCACACAGGAGAGAGACCAUACAAUUGUAAGGAAUGUGGGAAGAGUUUUGGCUGGGCCUCGUGUCUUUUGAAACAUCAGAGACUGCACAGUGGAGAAAAACCAUUCAAAUGUGAAGAGUGUGGGAAAAGAUUUACUCAGAAUUCACAGCUUCAUUCUCAUCAAAGAGUGCACACUGGAGAAAAGCCAUACAAAUGUGAUGAGUGUGGGAAGGGCUUCAGCUGGUCCUCAACUCGUCUGACCCAUCAGAGACGCCACAGCAGAGAAACACCUCUCAAAUGUGAGCAGCAUGGGAAGAACAUUGUACAGAAUUCAUUCUCUAAAGUGCAAGAAAAAGUUCACAGUGUAGAAAAGCCAUACAAAUGUGAGGACUGUGGGAAGGGCUACAACAGGCGCUUGAAUCUUGAUAUGCAUCAGAGGGUCCACAUGGGAGAGAAAACAUGGAAGUGUAGGGAGUGUGAUAUGUGCUUUAGUCAGGCCUCAAGCCUUCGACUUCAUCAGAAUGUUCAUGUUGGAGAAAAACCUUAGUGAUGUGAUGGUGCAAUAAAGUCUUCACUCAGUCUUCAUGAAUGCAGUCUCAUCUGAAAGUUCACAAAGGAGAGACACAUUAAAAUAUGAGGCACAUAGUAAGCACUUCCCUUUGAGUAUUUUAUCUCUGAAUCCAUGCUGGUGAUAAAUUUCACCCAUUCUUGGAAGAGGGAAAACAUUUGUUUAAGAUAACAUCAGUGCUUCAGCCAUAGCUCAGCAUGCCCCAGUAGUCUCAGGACCACCAUAAUGGAGAAUCCUUGUAAAUGGUGCAAUAAAGCUUCAUUCAGAAGUUUGAUAAUUACAGCUAUCAUUCAGGAGACAGGCCUUAGAAAGAGUAAGAGUUCAUGAAUUUACCAGACUAAUGGUGGACAUGUCCAAAUUGAUGUCCACUAGAAUGUAAACUACAUGUGUCUUUGCUGCUAAGUCGUCACAGCCUUAACAUUGAUUAGCACUUUGUAUGUGUUCAGUACUUGUUUGUUAAAUCAAUGAAAGGAUAAAACAUAUGUAUGGAUUUGGAUACAAUUUUGUGUAUCCAAAAAGGGAAGCCUGCAAAAAAUAAUUCUGGGAAACAUGAGUUGAAAUGCAGAGUAAACUCAGUACUGCAAUCCAUAGCAAUAUUUUGCAUAUUAUUAUUUUUUCUUUUAAAUUUUUUUCUUGAUCAGAUUUAUCAUAUUCAUUGAACAUUAUUUUAUUGCACUUGGCUCCUGGCUUCCCCCCAUCCUGUGCUCUGAAGUCAGAGUAUUAUUUGUGGCUCUAUGAAAUGUCCAUUGCUUGUAUACGGUAUAAAUUUAAUUAUCUUUUGUAGUUUUUCUCACAGUAUAGACUGAAAAGGUUUGGUUAAUUUUGCAAUAACAGACCACUGCAUAUUUCACAAUUAAGUGUUUUCAACAGUAUUAAGGCAAGAUUUACAGUAACACUUUUAAAGUGCCAGAUGUACAUUGACAGAAAUUUUCUUAGUCAAUCCUAGAUUGAUCAUGAUUUGUGAUUUCUAUGCAGGCCUUGGUAUGAUUGCCUUUUAAUUGCUGUACAAUUUCUUUUUUUUUUUUAACUUCUCUGGUAUAAAAUAUUCUAAAUUUGAAUGACAGCUUUUGUCAACCUUCUUAUCCAAUAUUCUUCCACCAACGCUAUGAAACAGGAAGAGAAAAUGGAGUUUGGUAAUUUCAUCAAAUAUAUUCAUUAUUGGGGGCAGGAGUAACAUUUAAAUCCUCCUCUUUAUUGCUGGCAGUAAAAAUAUGUCUUUUGGAGAGCAGAACAUGCCAGAAUGUAUAAGGUGCAACUGUUUGAUAUGAAAACCAUAGGAUAGGAAACUAUGCCUAUGACACUAAAACUCCAAAAAGUAGAAGACCACAUUGAUGAUGUCACUGCAUUUUAAAAUGGAAAGAACAAGUGUUCAAGAACAGGAAUUUGUGUGAAUUGCAUUUAUUCCUAUAAUAAUAUGAACUCAAUGAGAUGAUGACAUAGACACAAUAACAAAAGGAGAAAAACAAUGUGGCUUUUUUUAGCCUUCAUAACCUAAUCAAAUAAAUAUCUUUGUGUGUUUUA